GCUCCUUCCUCAGCGGCGGGAAGCUGGCGGCAGCGGCGGUGGCGGUGGCUGAGCAGAGGACCCGGCGGGCGGCCUCGCGGGUCAGGACACAAUGUUUGCACGAGGACUGAAGAGGAAAUGUGUUGGCCACGAGGAAGACGUGGAGGGAGCCCUGGCCGGCUUGAAGACAGUGUCCUCAUACAGCCUGCAGCGGCAGUCGCUCCUGGACAUGUCUCUGGUGAAGUUGCAGCUUUGCCACAUGCUUGUGGAGCCCAACCUGUGCCGCUCAGUCCUCAUUGCCAACACGGUCCGGCAGAUCCAAGAGGAGAUGACGCAGGAUGGGACGUGGCGCACAGUGGCACCCCAGGCUGCAGAGCGGGCGCCGCUCGACCGCUUGGUCUCCACGGAGAUCCUGUGCCGUGCAGCGUGGGGGCAAGAGGGGGCACAUCCUGCUCCUGGCUUGGGGGACGGCCACACACAGGGUCCAGUUUCUGACCUUUGCCCAGUCACCUCAGCACAGGCACCAAGGCACCUGCAGAGCAGCGCCUGGGAGAUGGAUGGCCCUCGAGAAAACAGAGGAAGCUUUCACAAGUCACUUGAUCAGAUAUUUGAAACGCUGGAGACUAAAAACCCCAGCUGCAUGGAAGAGCUGUUCUCAGACGUGGACAGCCCCUACUACGACCUGGACACAGUACUGACAGGCAUGAUGGGGGGUGCCAGGCCGGGCCCCUGCGAAGGGCUCGAGGGCUUGGCUCCGGCCACCCCAGGCCCUAGCUCCAGCUGCAAGUCCGACCUGGGCGAGCUGGACCACGUGGUGGAGAUCCUGGUGGAGACCUGAGCAGGAGCCCUGAGUGCUCACAGCCGCCUCUGACGCAUUGACACGUGAGCACUGGCUCCCACGGAGGGUGCGCCUGCCGCCAGCGGCCCAGCCUUGCUGCCCUGUCUGCUGAUUCUGAGAAAUCCCAGAACAGCCCAUUACCAGUGGGGCUGCAGCCCUAGGCCCGUCCCACUCACCUCCCCCCUGUGGAGCGCCAGGCAGAGGCUGUUCUGGAAGGCUUCUUGUCUUCUGACGUCCCCACAGCCCUGGGCCCCUCGUGUCUCUUUGUGUCCCCCACUGUAGAGGACGGUGAGCCGCAGCUGCAUCAACCUCCUUUUACCUUUAGAUAGGUGAAUUUUUACAAUUCAGUUUUACAUGUUUUGGGCAGUAUUUUGUCUUAAGAUAUAUUUUUUAAACUUUUUAUACCUUAUCUCUUUAGAUUUUUUCAGCUAUUUUCUUAAAAGUAUAUUUUUUCUAUAAACAUCCUUUGCUGCUACAUUAGAACUUUUAUAGCCUAAACAAUUGCAGUUGGUGUGUUUCAUUUUUUUAAGGUUUAAAUAAGGGUUUUUUGUUUUGUUUUGUUUUUUGCAGUGAGCAUCACUACAGUCUCAGUCAACAGUGUGAAUGUAUCAUGUUUUACUUUAAAUGUGUGUGUGAUACUUCUUCAUUAUGUCCUGCGCUGCAGUGAGACCUGGGUGAAAAUCAGGAGCCGCACACAGCCACAUCUUCCUAGACCUAAGAGUAAAUUAUGGAGGAUUUUAUUUAUGUCUAUUUAUAUGUAAAUGUCAUUGAAGACAAAGGUCAAAUAUUUGUCUGUUUGUAGAUCACAGGCACCAGUUGGUCUUCAGGGACCUCAUAGCCCCUCGGUGGUGCCUUCUCAAGGCAGUGUUCCUGGAGGCUCCCAUCAGGGUCAGCCCAUGCACCUGCCCUGGGUGAGGAAGUAGCAUUGCUGCUGGAUGAGAAACGCCUGCGCUGCUCUGUUAGACUGGUGCUGAAACAAAAGGUUAAGGCUAGGUUGAAGUCUAGAAUGAAAGAAAUCUGAAUCCAUGUCAUUCAUAACCCCUUGAUCUGUAGUGUCAUGGGUGCUGCCGCAGGCAGGGAGUGAGCUGGGGGUGCCUGCAGCCUUCCACUCCUGCCCCGCCUCACCCCACAUGCUCCCUGUUUCUCAUGCUUUCUCUAACUUCCUCACCCCUUAACCAAAAAGGUGUGUUUUCUUUUGUGCAUAUAGCCAUUCUUAAAUAUCAGUGAUGUAAACCUCACUUUAUUAAAAAAUUAUCCAGCAAACAAAAUGGGAAUGUGGUGUUAGUUACGACCACGGCCUGACCCUCCAGCAACCUUUCUGCAGGAUCAGUUCUGCUGUAUUAUCUGGUGGUGCUUUCUAAGGUGGGGAAAGGAAUUGCACUUGGCUGCAUUAAAUGGACGCUGGGUUACUUUUAUUUCCCCCCCCCACAGGGUUGCAGAGCAAAUUCUUUUUACAUUGUUCAGCGCCCGGCUGGAGUUGGGGGUGUCCACGACCUCUGACAGCCCCCGAUGUCGAAAGUUAAUCCUCAUGGACCCUAGUUUAAAGGGUAUGUGUUUUAUAGGAAUAAAUCUAAAGCACUAUUUUGUUUCUGUAUAGCAUUUUUAUCUUUUAGAAACAUCAUUUGUUCAGC